ACUAUCGCUUACCUACCUCCCUCUGCAGGAACCCGGCGAUAUGGCUGCCGCUGUGCCCCGCGCCGCAUUUCUCUCCCCGCUGCUUCCCCUUCUCCUGGGCUUCCUGCUCCUCUCCGCUCCGCAUGGCGGCAGCGGCCUGCACACCAAGGGCGCCCUUCCCCUGGAUACGGUCACUUUCUACAAGGUCAUUCCCAAAAGCAAGUUCGUCUUGGUGAAGUUCGACACCCAGUACCCCUACGGUGAGAAGCAGGAUGAGUUCAAGCGUCUUGCUGAAAACUCGGCUUCCAGCGAUGAUCUCUUGGUGGCAGAGGUGGGGAUCUCAGAUUAUGGUGACAAGCUGAACAUGGAGCUGAGUGAGAAAUACAAGCUGGACAAAGAGAGCUACCCAGUCUUCUACCUCUUCCGGGAUGGGGACUUUGAGAACCCAGUCCCAUACACUGGGGCAGUUAAGGUUGGAGCCAUCCAGCGCUGGCUGAAGGGGCAAGGGGUCUACCUAGGUAUGCCUGGUUGCCUGCCUGUAUACGACGCCCUGGCCGGGGAGUUCAUCAGGGCCUCUGGUGUGGAGGCCCGCCAGGCCCUCUUGAAGCAGGGGCAAGAUAACCUCUCAAGUGUGAAGGAGACUCAGAAGAAGUGGGCCGAGCAAUACCUGAAGAUCAUGGGGAAGAUCUUAGACCAAGGGGAGGACUUCCCAGCAUCAGAGAUGACACGGAUCGCCAGGCUGAUUGAGAAGAACAAGAUGAGUGACGGGAAGAAGGAGGAGCUCCAGAAGAGCUUAAACAUCCUGACUGCCUUCCAGAAGAAGGGGGCCGAGAAAGAGGAGCUGUAAAAAGGCUGUCUGUGAUUUUCCAGGGUUUGGUGGGGGUAGGGAGGGGAGAGUUAACCUGCUGGCUGUGAGUCCCUUGUGGAAUAUAAGGGGGUAGUGGGAAAAGUGGUACUAACCCACGAUUCUGAGCCCUGAGUAUGCCUGGACAUUGAUGCUAACAUGACCAUGCUUGGGAUGUCUCUAGCUGGUCUGGGGAUAGCUGGAGCACUUACUCAGGUGGCUGGUGAAAUGACACCUCAGAAGGAAUGAGUGCUAUAGAGAGGAGAGAGGAGUGUACUGCCCAGGUCUUUGACAGAUGUAAUUCUCAUUCAAUUAAAGUUUCAGUGUUUUGGUUAAGUGGACCUGAAGCCAUUCUUUUUUCUUUUCAAAUUAUACUUUCGUCUAUGACCUGCUUUCCUCUUUGAAUCUAAGCUGGUAUAGACUCCACUUUCCCAGGGUAACAAACUAUCCUCAUAACACUGUGGAAACUGGCAUACCUUUGUUAUUUUCCAGUGAUAUUCAGACUGACAUGGAUUGACUGUCAAUGGUAAAGUUUGUCUAUUUUCCAGUCCUUAAAACUCAAUAGCAGUAUUGAUGAAUAUAUUGAACCAACAUUGAUGGACCAUGGUGUAAUUAUUUUCCAUGCUUUGUGAGGUACACAUAGCAAAUUCUUAGUUUUACUGAUAUAUUCUGUGACUUGGAUUUACACAGCUAAAUGAUAUAGUCCGAUUUCAAAAUUAAAAAAUAUUUUCCAUCUAAAUCACUAUCACUAAAUAAAUACUAACUUCUAGAAAGCAGAAUAAAGAGCACUUGUGCCAACA